GUCUCUCUGAUCUGGCCCAUCCGGCUUCGGAGGGAGGCGAGGGUGGGUGAGCAAAGGGAUUGGGUCUGUGGGGUCCAGGCCCGAACCCCUGAAGACGGGCUCCGCCCCCGGCACCCGCUCGCGCCCCGCCCCCGGCUGGAGGAGUCUCUCCUGGACCAUCCGAACCUAGCCUGUCCCGGCCCGCAGCCUCUAUGGAGGCUCCUGCCGGGCCGUAGAGCCCUUCGCCCCCUGGGGACCCACCCGUCUAUAAGGUCCGUUUGGCCUGCAGCAGCCUGAGUCCGUAAUGCUGGGCACUGUUCAUGGGAUCGGCCCCCUAUGGAGCCCUGUGUCUAUAGGGGACUCCUACGGUCCCUAGGGUUCGGCCCCGUCCAUAAUGACUCCAUAUACAGGGCCUUCCAUCGCUCUAUAGGGCUCAGCCCUCGGCUUCCAGAGCCUGUCAGCAGUGGCCGUACCCUUCGCCGGGACUGCCGGGUCUCCGGGACCUCUUCGAUCUACAAGGUCAUGUUAUGCCUAUAGAGGUCGCAUUUGCAGGGCCUCACCCCGGGUAGAGGGUCCUCUCCAGGUUUUUACGGCCUGUCCCCGCUCUAAGGGUCAGUGCAGGAGGCGGCGAUGGCCCUGGGCAAGGUUCUGGCCAUGGCACUGGUUUUGGCCUUGGCCGUGCUGGGGUCGCUGUCCCCUGGGGCCCGGGCGGGGGACUGCAAGGGGCAGCGGCAGGUGCUGCGGGAGGCGCCAGGCUUCGUGACGGAUGGUGCGGGCAACUACAGCGUCAAUGGCAACUGCGAGUGGCUCAUCGAGGCCCCAAGCCCCCAGCACCGGAUCCUGCUGGACUUCCUUUUCCUGGACACAGAGUGCACGUAUGACUACCUGUUCGUGUAUGACGGUGACUCCCCGCGAGGGCCGCUGCUUGCCAGUCUAAGUGGGAGCACCCGACCUCCGCCCAUCGAAGCUUCCUCAGGCAAGAUGCUGCUGCACCUCUUCAGUGAUGCCAACUACAACCUGCUGGGCUUUAACGCCUCAUUCCGCUUCUCCCUGUGCCCGGGUGGCUGCCAGAGCCACGGGCAGUGCCAGCCACCGGGUGUGUGUGCCUGCGAGCCGGGCUGGGGGGGUCCUGACUGUGGCCUGCAGGAGUGCUCAGCCUACUGUGGCAGCCACGGCACCUGCGCCUCGCCCCUGGGACCAUGCCGCUGUGAGCCUGGCUUCUUGGGACGUGCCUGUGACCUGCACCUGUGGGAGAACCAGGGGGCUGGGUGGUGGCACAACGUGAGUGCCAGGGACCCUGCCUUCUCUGCCCGUAUUGGGGCAGCUGGCGCCUUCCUGUCCCCACCAGGGCUGCUGGCAGUUUUCGGAGGCCAGGACCUCAACAAUGCCCUGGGUGACCUCGUCCUAUACAACUUCUCCGCCAACACCUGGGAGUCUUGGGACCUGAGUCCUGCCCCGGCUGCCCGUCACUCCCAUGUGGCCGUGGCCUGGGCCGGCUCCCUGGUACUGAUGGGUGGUGAGCUGGCUGACGGCUCGCUCACCAACGACGUGUGGGCCUUCAGUCCACUGGGCAGGGGCCACUGGGAGCUCCUGGCACCACCUGCCUCCAGCUCCUCGGGGCCCCCAGGCCUGGCAGGUCACGCGGCUGCCCUGGUGGAUGAUGUCUGGCUAUAUGUGUCUGGAGGCCGCACCCCGCACGACCUCUUCUCCUCUGGCCUCUUCCGUUUCCGCCUUGACAGCACCAGCGGGGGCUAUUGGGAGCAGGUGAUUCCGGCAGGCGGACGGCCCCCUGCUGCCACUGGCCACUCCAUGGUGUUCCAUGCCCCCUCCCGUGCCCUGCUGGUCCAUGGUGGACACCGGCCCUCCACUGCCCGGUUCUCUGUGCGAGUGAACUCCACUGAGCUUUUCCACGUGGAUCGGCAUGUGUGGACGACGCUGAAGGGGCGGGAUGGGCUUCAGGGCCCAAGGGAGCGAGCCUUCCACACAGCCAGUGUUCUGGGCAAUUACAUGGUGGUCUAUGGGGGCAAUGUGCACACCCAUUACCAGGAGGAAAAGUGCUACGAAGAUGGCAUCUUCUUCUACCACCUUGGCUGCCAUCAAUGGGUGUCAGGAGCUGAGCUUGCCCCGCCAGGAACCCCUGAGGGCCGAGCAGCGCCUCCCAGUGGUCGGUACUCACAUGUAGCUGCGGUGCUUGGUGGCAGCGUCCUGUUGGUGGCUGGGGGGUACAGCGGCCGGCCCCGUGGGGACUUGAUGGCGUACAAGGUGCCCCCCUUUGUGUUCCAGGCACCUGCCCCUGACUACCACUUGGACUACUGCUCCAUGUACACAGACCACAGCGUCUGCUCCCGGGACCCGGAAUGCAGUUGGUGCCAAGGAGCCUGCCAAGCUGCACCCCCUCCUGGGACCCCCUUGGGGGCUUGUCCAGCCGCCAGCUGCCUGGGCCUGGGCCGCCUCCUGGGUGACUGCCAGGCCUGCCUGGCCUUCAGCAGCCCCACAGCCCCUCCACGGGGACCUGGCACCCUGGGCUGGUGCGUGCACAAUGAGAGCUGCCUCCCUAGGCCUGAGCAGGCCCGCUGCCGAGGGGAGCAGAUCUCAGGCACUGUGGGCUGGUGGGGGCCUGCGCCUGUCUUCGUCACGUCCCUGGAGGCCUGCGUCACCCAGAGCUUCCUGCCUGGCCUGCACUUGCUCACCUUUCAGCAGCCGCCCAAUACCUCCCAGCCUGACAAGGUCUCAAUUGUCCGCAGCACGACCAUCACCCUAACACCCAGCGCAGAGACAGAUGUGUCCCUGGUCUACCGUGGCUUCAUCUACCCAAUGCUGCCUGGAGGGCCAGGUGGACCAGGGGCUGAGGACGUGGCCGUGUGGACGCGGGCCCAGCGCCUACACGUCCUGGCCCGGAUGGCCCGUGGCCCUGACACGGAGAACAUGGAGGAGGUGGGGCGCUGGGUGGCUCAUCAGGAGAAGGAGACGCGGCGGCUGCAGCGCCCUGGGUCUGCUCGCCUCUUCCCUCUGCCUGGGCGGGACCACAAGUAUGCAGUAGAGAUCCAGGGCCAGCUCAAUGGCUCGGCAGGCCCUGGGCACAGCGAGCUAACUCUGCUGUGGGAUCGGACUGGUGUGCCAGGAGGCAGCGAGAUCUCCUUCUUCUUCCUGGAGCCCUACCGCUCGUCGUCCUGCACCUCCUAUUCUUCCUGCCUGGGCUGCUUGGCAGACCAGGGCUGUGGCUGGUGCCUGACCAGUGCCACCUGCCACCUGCGCCAGGGCGGAGCCCAUUGCGGGGAUGACGGGGCUGGUGGGUCCCUGCUGGUGCUGGUGCCUACCCUCUGCCCACUCUGCGAGGAGCAUCGGGACUGCCACGCCUGCACCCAGGACCCCUUCUGUGAGUGGCAUCAGAGCACCAGCCGCAAAGGGGACGCGGCAUGCAGCCGGCGGGGCCGGGGUCGGGGUGCCCUGAAGAGUCCAGAGGAGUGUCCCCCGCUCUGCAGCCAGCGACUGACCUGUGAGGACUGCCUGGCCAACUCUAGCCAGUGCGCCUGGUGCCAGUCCACCCACACCUGCUUCCUGUUUGCUGCCUACUUGGCCCGGUACCCACACGGGGGCUGUCGAGGCUGGGACGACAGUGUACACUCGGAGCCACGGUGCCGGAGCUGCGAUGGCUUCCUGACCUGCCAUGAGUGUCUGCAGAGCCACGAGUGUGGCUGGUGUGGCAAUGAGGACAACCCCACACUGGGACGGUGCCUACAGGGGGACUUCUCAGGGCCCCUCGGUGGGGGUAACUGCUCCCUGUGGGUGGGGGAGGGCCUGGGGCUUCCCGUGGCCCUCCCUGCCCGCUGGGCAUACGCCCGCUGUCCUGACGUGGAUGAGUGUCGCCUGGGCCUGGCCCGGUGCCACCCGCGGGCGACCUGCCUGAACACGCCCCUCAGCUACGAGUGUCACUGCCAGCGGGGCUACCAGGGUGAUGGCAUCUCACACUGCAACCGCACGUGCUUGGAGGACUGUGGCCAUGGUGUGUGCAGUGGCCCCCCGGACUUUACCUGCGUGUGUGACCUAGGCUGGACAUCAGACCUGCCCCCUCCCACACCCGCCCCGGGUCCGCCAGCCCCCCGCUGCUCCCGGGACUGUGGCUGCAGCUUCCACAGCCACUGCCGCAAGCGGGGCCCUGGCUUCUGCGACGAGUGCCAGGACUGGACAUGGGGGGAGCACUGCGAACGAUGCCGGCCCGGCAGCUUCGGCAACGCCACAGGCUCUAGGGGCUGCCGGCCCUGCCAGUGCAACGGGCACGGGGACCCACGCCGUGGCCACUGCGACAACCUCAGUGGGCUCUGCUUCUGCCAGGACCACACCGAGGGUGCCCACUGCCAGCUCUGCUCCCCAGGCUAUUAUGGGGAUCCCCGGGCCGGUGGUUCCUGCUUUCGGGAGUGUGGGGGUCGCGCCCUCCUCACCAACGUGUCCUCAGUGGCACUGGGCUCACGCCGGGUCGGGGGGCUGCUGCCUCCAGGUGGCGGGGCUGCAAGAGCCGGGCCUGGCCUGUCCUACUGUGUGUGGGUUGUCUCGGCCACUGAGGAGCUACAGCCCUGUGCUCCCGGGACCCUCUGUCCCCCACUCACCCUCACCUUCUCCCCCGACAGCAGCACCCCCUGCACGCUGAGCUACGUCCUGGCGUUUGAUGGAUUCCCACGCUUCCUGGACACUGGUGUUGUCCAGUCGGACCGCAGCCUCAUAGCUGCCUUCUGCGGCCAGCGACGGGACAGGCCCCUCACUGUUCAGGCCCUGUCUGGGCUGCUCGUGCUGCACUGGGAGGCCAAUGGCUCCUCAUCCUGGGGCUUCAAUGCUUCGGUGGGCUCUGCCCGCUGUGGGUCAGGGGGCCCCGGGAGCUGUCCCGUCCCCCAGGAAUGCGUGCCCCAGGACGGUGCUGCAGGUGCGGGGCUCUGCCGAUGUCCUCAGGGCUGGGCUGGCCCACACUGCCGCAUGGCUCUGUGUCCUGAGAACUGCAAUGCCCACACUGGGGCAGGAACUUGUAACCAGAGCCUGGGUGUGUGCAUCUGUGCCGAGGGCUUCGGGGGCCCCGACUGCGCCACCAAGCUGGAUGGCGGGCAGCUGGUCUGGGAGACCCUCAUGGACAGCCGCCUCUCAGCCGACACUGCCAGCCGCUUCCUGCACCGCCUGGGCCACACCAUGGUGGAUGGACCCGAUGCCACCUUGUGGAUGUUUGGGGGCCUGGGCCUGCCCCAGGGGCUGCUGGGAAACCUGUACAGGUACUCAGUGAGUGAGCGGCGGUGGACACAGAUGCUGGCGGGAGCCGAGGACGGGGGCCCAGGCCCAUCGCCCCGCUCCUUCCAUGCAGCCGCAUAUGUGCCCGCUGGCCGUGGUGCCAUGUAUCUGCUGGGGGGACUUACCGCUGGAGGCGUCACCCGUGAUUUCUGGGUCCUCAACCUCACCACCCUGCAAUGGCGGCAGGAGAAGGCCCCCCAGACCGUGGAGCUGCCAGCCGUUGCUGGUCACACCCUUACUGCCCGCCGAGGCCUGUCUCUGCUCCUGGUGGGCGGUUACUCCCCGGAAAAUGGCUUCAACCAGCAGCUGCUGGAGUACCAGCUGGCAACCGGCACCUGGGUGUCAGGAGCCCAGAGUGGGACACCCCCCACAGGUCUCUAUGGUCACUCUGCUGUCUACCACGAGGCCACCGACUCCCUCUACGUGUUUGGGGGGUUCCGAUUCCAUGUGGAGCUGGCGGCCCCAUCCCCCGAGCUCUACUCCCUGCACUGUCCUGACCGCACCUGGAGUCUGCUGGCCCCUUCUCAGGGGGCAAAGCGAGAUCGUAUGAGGAAUGUGCGUGGCUCAUCUCGGGGUCUGGGCCAAGUUCCUGGGGAGCAGCCUGGGUCAUGGGGGUUCCGGGAAGUCAGGAAGAAGAUGGCUCUGUGGGCUGCUCUUGCUGGUACAGGAGGUUUCCUGGAGGAAAUCUCACCUCACCUGAAGGAGCCCCGCCCCCGGCUUUUCCACGCCUCAGCCCUGUUAGGGGACACCAUGGUGGUUCUUGGGGGGCGCUCGGACCCUGACGAGUUCAGCAGCGACGUUCUGCUCUACCAGGUCAACUGCAAUGCCUGGCUUCUGCCCGACCUCACCCGCUCGGCCUCUGUGGGGCCCCCAAUGGAGGAGUCUGUGGCCCAUGCUGUGGCAGCAGUCGGGAGCCGCCUGUAUAUCUCUGGGGGUUUCGGGGGAGUGGCCCUGGGCCGCCUGCUGGCACUGACCCUGCCCCCUGACCCCUGCCGCCUGCUGUCCUCACCUGAAGCUUGUAACCAGUCUGGGGCCUGCACCUGGUGCCAUGGGGCCUGCUUGUCCGGGGAUCAGGCCCACAGGCUGGGCUGCGGGGGCUCCCCCUGCUCCCCAAUGCCUCGCUCCCCGGAGGAAUGUCGACGUCUCCGGACCUGCAGUGAGUGCCUGGCCCGCCAUCCUCGGACCCUGCAACCUGGAGAUGGAGAGGCGUCCACCCCCCGCUGUAAGUGGUGUACCAACUGCCCCGAAGGUGCUUGCAUUGGACGCAAUGGGUCCUGCACCUCUGAGAAUGACUGUCGGAUCAACCAGCGAGAGGUCUUCUGGGCAGGGAACUGCUCCGAGGCUGCGUGCGGGGCUGCUGACUGCGAGCAGUGCACGCGGGAGGGCAAGUGCAUGUGGACGCGGCAGUUCAAGAGGACAGGGGAGACCCGCCGCAUCCUCUCCGUGCAGCCCACCUAUGACUGGACGUGCUUCAGCCACUCUCUGCUGAAUGUGUCCCCCAUGCCGGUGGAAUCAUCACCCCCACUGCCCUGCCCCACCCCUUGUCACCUCCUACCCAACUGUACCUCCUGCCUGGACUCUAAGGGAGCAGAUGGGGGCUGGCAGCACUGUGUUUGGAGCAGCAGCCUGCAGCAGUGUCUGAGCCCUUCCUACCUGCCCCUGCGAUGUAUGGCCGGAGGCUGUGGGCGGCUGCUCCGGGGACCUGAGAGCUGCUCCCUGGGCUGUGCUCAGGCAACUCAGUGCGCCUUGUGCCUGCGGCGCCCCCAUUGCGGCUGGUGUGCCUGGGGGGGCCAGGAUGGGGGUGGCCGCUGCAUGGAGGGUGGACUCAGCGGCCCCCGUGAUGGGCUGACAUGUGGGCGUCCGGGGGCCUCCUGGGCCUUCCUGUCCUGCCCCCCUGAGGACGAGUGUGCAAACGGGCACCACGACUGCAACGAGACGCAGAAUUGCCACGACCAGCCCCACGGCUAUGAGUGCAGCUGCAAGACCGGCUAUACCAUGGACAACAUGACAGGGCUGUGCCGCCCUGUGUGCGCCCAGGGCUGCGUGAACGGCUCAUGUGUGGAGCCCGACCACUGCCGCUGCCACUUUGGCUUUGUGGGCCGCAACUGCUCCACGGAAUGCCGCUGCAACCGCCACAGUGAAUGCGCUGGUGUUGGGGCGCGUGACCACUGCUUGCUCUGCCGCAACCACACCAAGGGCAGCCACUGUGAGCAGUGCCUCCCGCUGUUUGUGGGUUCAGCUGUCGGAGGCGGGACCUGCCGGCCCUGCCACGCCUUUUGUCGUGGAAAUAGCCACAUCUGCAUCUCCAGGAAGGAGUUACAAAUGUCCAAGGGAGAGCCAAAGAAGUACUCACUGGACCCAGAGGAGAUUGAAAACUGGGUGACAGAGGGUCCUAGUGAAGACGAGGCCGUGUGCGUGAACUGCCAGAAUAACAGCUAUGGGGAGAAAUGCGAGAGCUGCCUGCAGGGCUACUUCCUCCUGGACGGGAAGUGCACCAAAUGCCAGUGUAAUGGCCACGCGGACACAUGUAACGAGCAGGAUGGGACGGGCUGUCCAUGUCAGAAUAACACAGAGACGGGCACAUGCCAGGGCAGCUCCCCCAGUGACCGUCGAGACUGCUACAAGUACCAGUGCGCCAAGUGCCGGGAAUCAUUUCACGGGAGUCCGCUGGGCGGCCAGCAGUGCUACCGCCUCAUCUCGGUGGAGCAGGAGUGCUGCCUGGACCCCACGUCCCAGACCAACUGCUUCCAUGAGCCCAAACGCCGGGCGCUAGGCCCCGGCCGCACUGUCCUCUUUGGCGUGCAGCCCAAAUUCACCAACGUGGACAUCCGCCUGACGCUGGACGUGACCUUCGGGGCCGUGGACCUCUAUGUCUCCACCUCCUAUGACACCUUCGUGGUCCGUGUGGCCCCUGACACUGGCGUCCAUACUGUACACAUCCAGCCACCCCCAGCCCCACCACCUCCACCACCCCCUGCAGAUGGUGGGCCCCGGGGGGCUGGGGAUCCAGGAGGAGCAGGGGCCAGCAGUGGGCCGGGCGCCCCAGCAGAGCCACGGGUACGGGAGGUAUGGCCGCGGGGCCUGAUUACCUACGUGACGGUGACGGAGCCGUCGGCAGUGCUGGUGGUCCGCGGCGUGCGGGACCGGCUGGUCAUCACCUACCCACACGAGCACCAUGCCCUCAAGUCGAGCCGCUUCUACCUGCUGCUGCUGGGCGUGGGAGACCCAAGUGGGCCCGGCGCCAACGGCUCAGCCGACUCGCAGGGCCUGCUCUUCUUCCGGCAGGACCAGGCCCACAUUGACCUGUUUGUCUUCUUCUCCGUCUUCUUCUCCUGCUUCUUCCUCUUCCUCUCACUCUGUGUGCUCCUCUGGAAGGCCAAGCAGGCUCUGGACCAGCGGCAGGAGCAGCGCCGGCACUUGCAGGAGAUGACCAAGAUGGCCAGCCGCCCCUUCGCCAAGGUCACCGUCUGCUUCCCACCUGACCCUACUGCCCCGGCCUCCGCCUGGAAGCCGGCUGGGCUCCCACCUCCCGCCUUCCGCCGCUCUGAGCCCUUCCUGGCACCCCUGCUGCUGACAGGGGCCGGUGGGCCCUGGGGACCCAUGGGAGGGGGCUGCUGCCCACCAGCCAUCCCCGCCACCACUGCUGGGCUGCGAGCUGGGCCCAUCACUCUCGAGCCCACAGAAGAUGGCAUGGCUGGCGUGGCCACACUGCUGCUCCAGCUGCCUGGCGGGCCCCAUGCACCCAACGGCGCCUGCCUGGGGUCAGCCCUCGUCACACUGCGGCACAGGCUGCACGAGUACUGUGGGGGUGGUGGGGGUGCUGGGGGCAGUGGGCAUGGGACUGGUGCGGGCCGGAAGGGACUGUUGAGCCAGGACAACCUCACCAGCAUGUCCCUCUGACAUGCCCAGGGUUCUCAUCCACAGCAGCUGGGUCACCUGAUAGGGCCGCCCUGGACUUGGGGUCCCUCCACCUGGGGGCCCCUGGACACUGUCUACUUGGAGACCACUGGCCCCCUUCCCCCAGGGUUGCCCAGAUGGGGCCUCCUUUGUUCUGCAUUCAGCAGCUAUUUAUCGAGUACCUACUCUGUCAGGCACUGUCAUAGGCGUGGGGCAAAGCAGGAACCAAGAGACGAGGUUCCCUGAUCUCAUGGGACUUAGGUUCUGGUGAAGGGAGACAAUCAGUGCACAUGCACACACCCCACACGCAUACACACAUGAACACAUGCACAUGUGCACACACAAGUAAGAUGGCUUCAGAGAGGGAGAAGCACUGUGAGGCCUCCAGAGGAUGUGGCAGUGAGGGACGAUGGGGUGAAGUCAGCUGGGCAUUCAAAGAAGCUAGACUGAGAACGCCUGAGAAGAACCAGCUACGGGAAGAGCUUUGGGAAGCAAAGGCAGAGGCCCUGGGGUGGGAGCAGGCUUGUUUUAUUGGAAGGACCAGAAAACUGGUAAGUGUGACCCAGAUCAAGUGUGAGGAGAUGAGGCUGGGGAUAGUCAGGGGCUGGAUCACCCAGGGCCUUGUGGGCCCCACAUAGGGUUUUGGGUUUUAUUCUCAGGGCAAUGGGAAGCUGUUGGAUGGUUUGAUGAAGGGGAGUGACAGGAUCCGAUGUACCUAUUUAAGAAUUUAAGAGGGUCGGGUGCGGUGGCUCAUGCCUAUAAUCCUAGCACUUUGAGAGGCCAAGGUGGGCUGAUCACAAGGUCAAGAGUUCGUGACCAGCCUGGCCAAUAUGGUGAAACCCCAUGUCUACUAAAAAUACAAAAAUUAGCUGGGCAUGGUGGCACACACUUGUAGUCCGAGCUACUCGGGAGGCUGAGGCAGAAGAAUCGCUUGAACCCAGGAGGCGGAGGUUGCAGUGAGCUCAGAUUGCGUCACUGCACUCCAACCUGGGUGACAGAGCGAGACUCCACCUCAAAAAAAAAAAAAAAAUUUAAGAGGUCACUCAGUUGUGCUGUGGAGAAUGGACCGGAGGGACAAGAGGGGCAGCAGGGAUGGUGGGCUGGAGUAGGGUGCUGGCAAUGAGGGAGUCUGGCUCAGAUGUGGGAUGUGUAUGGAAGAAUAUAAAUGAUGGUGUGGAUGUCAGGGUGAGGGAGGAGACAAAACCACGAUGACCCCUAGCUUUGUGGCCUGAACUGUGGGUGGCUGAGGGGAUCGUUAAUUGAAUGGGGCAGACUGAGGCUUGUGAGGAAGAUCAGAGUCUGGUUCUUGACAUGAGAUGCCCUUCAGACAUCUCUUCACUCAGGUCCAACUAGGGAUACAGAAACACUGAAUAUUUCAACAGCAGAAAUUGAAUGGGGGGAUUGAUAGCGCUGGCGAGGGAAGCAGCUGGAAAGAGACAGAUGGCACCCUGAGACAGCCCAGAGGUGAAUAGGACCCCCAGGCUGCAGGGAUAAAGCUCAGUGGUGGUGUUACCUCACCGGGGACCAGGGUCACACAGCAAAGCUGGAACAACAGAGGCGUGUUGUGGGGGAGCCUCAGAGGGGACAAAACCUCUGCCUGAGAUCCCACCCCAGGUGGGCAUGGGGGCCACUGAGGUUGGGGAUGAAAAUGCCGGUACCGUCAGUGCACAGCCCUGUUCCAGACAGUGCUGCCUGGAAGAUUUCUGGGCUCUCCUGAGGCGCCACCCCGCACCUGAGCCACCUCCUUGGACUCCUGUCCUCUACCCCUUGAGGACCUCCCUCCCUUCUACCCUAGCUGUCUUCUUGAACUUGGGACUCUCCUUUCCCAAGACUUCCAUCACUAGCUCCUGGAGGGACUGGACUUUGCAUCUUCCCUUCGCGUGGAGCCUCAGUGUGAGAGGCCCUAGCCAAUGCGUGCAUGUCAGAGGUGGUGGGGACCACAUCAGAAGAAGAGGGGGGUGAUGAAAUUAACAAAUAAAAAGUAUGGGGAAAA